GCGGACUCAGAAGCGAGCGGCACCCCGGGACCAUCCCACAGCAGAUCCAGUGGCCGCCAACGUCAGGCUGGAGUUGCCUCCUUCGUGGAUGUUGGAUGUGGAAGCCCAGGAGCCCCCCAAGGGGAAAUGGUCGACGCCGCCCUUCGACCCGCGCUUCCCCAGCCAGAACCAGAUCCGUAACUGCUACCAGAACUUCCUGGACUACCACCGCUGCCUCAAGACCAGGACCCGCCGCGGGAAGAGCACGCAGCCCUGCGAGUACUAUUUCCGCGUGUACCACUCGCUGUGCCCCAUCAGCUGGGUGGAGAGCUGGAACGAGCAGAUCAAGAACGGGAUUUUCGCCGGCAAAAUCUGACUGCCCCAGCGCGGCUUCCUCUGAAGAUGCAGUGAUCCUGCAUCUUUUUGUCUCGCGGAGCCCCGGGUCUCGGUUAUCCACCCCUACCUCCCAGUGUCUAAGCCACGAAUAAUGGUAGAUGCCUCGCGUUGACAGCUACGAGCCAGCCCAGGGUCCCCAGUUCUCAACACUGUCCCACCCAGAUGGCUCCAAGGCCAAGGAGUGCCGCUUGACAAAGCCCUAGGGUUCCAGCCUGGUCCUGCUGAGGGAGCCGUGAGACCAGUCAGCCUGGGGUGCUGGUUUUCCCAACGGGUACUCCCUGAGCUAUCAGCCUUCCAGAGGGGCUCCUAGGAGGGGGAAGCCCCAUCCUCUGACUGAAGCGGUCCUAUGAGGCCCUGUUCAACCCCAGGGUUCAAAGGACACACCCUAGAUGAGCCAUCCCCCAGGAUGACGCCACCUCUGAGAUCUUGGUCUCCUGGCUCCGUCUCUGACCACAACCCAAGAAUGGGGUGAGGGCACAGGGUGUGGACUCAACUACAGGAGGGCUUCCUGUUCAUGCAACGUCCCCAGAGCCUUGACGAAUGCACAGAGGCGCUGGCAGAACCACGGGGGCAGGACCCCUCUCUGAGUCACAGAAUGGAGCUAAGUUGGUGAGGUCACCCAGCCACCAGCCUUCGAGUUCCUUGUUUCCCUUGCUCUGGUCUCCACGUGUAUGAUGGGGUUCUCAGGCCCAGGCUUCGACCAGAGGACCCUCUGCCACCACCGUUUCUUCCUGUCCUUGAGCUACCUUGGUGAACUCAUGACCCCAGGCCCCUGCUCCACCAGGAUGUCCCCCAGGUCCUGCCAGCUGGGAAGUGCCAGCAUGAACGCCUCCAACUUCGUGGAAGCCAGGGUCCCCUGCAGCUGAGGGACGCCAAGCAGACACACCUGCCCUCCCCAGCCAGCUCCUGUCUGUAUGGGCGAGAUGACUGAGAGCGCCCACGUCCCUAAGGCUGUCCUGACCCUCCAUGCUGCGACAAGGACAGGGAAUGGUCGGUCACUAUGGGCCUGGUGUCUCCCCUCCCCCACCACCCGGUGCUGCCCAGCUCAAGCCAGAAGCUGACUUUGGCCGCCAUGGGGACAUCAGGCAAGGUCUGGAGACAUUUUUGGUUGGGGCAGAGGCAUGCUCCUGGCAUCGAGUGGGUGGAGACCAGAGAAGCCGCUCAACAUCCUGCAAUGCAUGGGACAGGCCCUGCCUAGAAACACCAGCUCAGCAUGGCAGCAGUGCGGAGGCCAGGAAACCCUGAUCGCCAGUUUCUAACGCCCUCACCAUUUUUAUUUUUAUUUUUAUUUUUUUUGAGACAGAGUUUCGCUCCUGUCACCCAGGCUGGAGUACAAUGAUGCGAUCUCAGCUCACUGCAACCUCUGCCUCCCGGGUUCAAGUGAUUCUCCUGCCUCAGCCUCCCGAGUAGCUGGGAUUACAGGCAUGCACCACCACGCCCAGCUUAUUUUGUAUUUUUAGUAGAGACGGGGUUUCUCCGUGUUGGUCAGGCUGGUCUCAAACUCCUGACCUCAGGCAAUCUGCCCACCUCAGCCUCCCAAAGUGCUGGGAUUACAGGCGUGAGCCACUGCACCCGGCUCACCACUAGUUUUUAGCCCUUUUUGUUGGGGGUGGGGUGGGGGCAGAGGAGAGGCGGAUACAGAAACUUGUGAGAAUGUGAUGAACGCUCUGAACCCCCUAUAAAAAAUGUGCAUGUAAAUAUAUACUCUCAACAUUUAAAA